AGCAUCUAUAAAGGCGGGCGGCGGCAGAGGCGCCAUUUUGCGAACGGCGAGCAGCGGCGGCGGCGCGGAGAGACGCAGCGGAGGUUUUCCUGGUUUCGGACCCCAGCGGCCGGAUGGUGAAAUCCUCCCUGCAGCGGAUCCUCAAUAGCCACUGCUUCGCCAGAGAGAAGGAAGGGGAUAAACCCAGCGCCACCAUCCACGCCAGCCGCACCAUGCCGCUCCUAAGCCUGCACAGCCGCGGCGGCAGCAGCAGUGAGAGUUCCAGGGUCUCCCUCCACUGCUGUAGUAACCCGGGUCCGGGGCCUCGGUGGUGCUCCUGAUGCCCCUCACCCACCCCUGAAGAUCCCAGGUGGGCGAGGGAAUAGUCAGAGGGAUCACAAUCUUUCAGCUAACUUAUUCUACUCCGAUGAUCGGCUGAAUGUAACAGAGGAACUAACGUCCAACGACAAGACGAGGAUUCUCAACGUCCAGUCCAGGCUCACAGACGCCAAACGCAUUAACUGGCGAACAGUGCUGAGUGGCGGCAGCCUCUACAUCGAGAUCCCGGGCGGCGCGCUGCCCGAGGGGAGCAAGGACAGCUUUGCAGUUCUCCUGGAGUUCGCUGAGGAGCAGCUGCGAGCCGACCAUGUCUUCAUUUGCUUCCACAAGAACCGCGAGGACAGAGCCGCCUUGCUCCGAACCUUCAGCUUUUUGGGCUUUGAGAUUGUGAGACCGGGGCAUCCCCUUGUCCCCAAGAGACCCGACGCUUGCUUCAUGGCCUACACGUUCGAGAGAGAGUCUUCGGGAGAGGAGGAGGAGUAGGGCCGCCUCGGGGCUGGGCAUCCGGCCCCUGGGGCCACCCCUUGUCAGCCGGGUGGGUAGGAACCGUAGACUCGCUCAUCUCGCCUGGGUUUGUCCGCAUGUUGUAAUCGUGCAAAUAAACGCUCACUCCGAAUUAGCGGUGUAUUUCUUGAAGUUUAAUAUUGUGUUUGUGAUACUGAAGUAUUUGCUUUAAUUCUAAAUAAAAAUUUAUAUUUUACUUUUUUAUUGCUGGUUUAAGAUGAUUCAGAUUAUCCUUGUACUUUGAGGAGAAGUUUCUUAUUUGGAGUCUUUUGGAAACAGUCUUAGUCUUUUAACUUGGAAAGAUGAGGUAUUAAUCCCCUCCAUUGCUCUCCAAAAGCCAAUAAAGUGAUUACACCCGA